GACCCAGGCGCCCACGCCUCUUUUCCCCGAAGGUCAGACAAAGGCAGAAGGGUUGGCUGGAUUCUUUCCCGGGCCGCGAAGGCCUGGGGAUCGCAAGUUGAGGAGGAGAAGACCGCAAACCCCUUUGGUUCAAGCAAGCUCUGCGGCAGGUUCCAUACAAGUAAAUCCGAAAAAAAGUGUGUGUGGGGGGGUCCACACCACUAAUUAUUAUGGCGAGGAAGAUAAAGAAGACAUGGACAGAAGGCGGAUGGCUCUGCGGCCUGGCUCCCGCAGACCGACCGCCUUCUUCUUCCAUUCGAGAUGGCUCGUACCGAACCUCCUUGCCUUCUUCCUGGGUCUCUCGGGGGCUGGACCAAUACAUCUGCCGAUGCCCUGGCCGAAUGGCAGGCGACAUCGGGUCCUGGACCCCCACACGCAGCUCAGUACCCACGAGGCCCCAGGCCGCUGGAAGCCUGUAGCUCCGCGGACGAUGAAAGCCUGCCCGCAGGUUCUCCUGGAGUGGUGAGCCUCUGUCGGAAGGGGGCGCCCACGUCUUUUUAAUGGUCCUAACACACCAGUGGAAUAAAUCUCUAAGAUUCCA